GAUAAUGCACCCAGCCCUGCUGAUGAGAACAGCGGAGGGAAAUGUCUCGAUGAACAGUUUCAUCUGGAUCACAAGGAUUUAGGAGGGACAGCUCCUAAAAUGGAGGGAGGUAGGACAGACUAAGAAGCCACAGAUUUUCCCUGCAAUGACAUUGAUCCUUUGGUGGGUAUUAAUUAGUUCACAGAAGAAACUCCAAAGAAAUUUGUGGAUUACUGGAUAGCAUGAAUUAUGGAGGAAAUAUUGCUGCUCUUCCUAAGUGAGAGACCUUUAGGGUGAAAUGACUCAUUUCCUCUGUUGAAUGGAAGCACCAUUCUUACAUAUUACUUCCACAUUAGGACACUAAUAUUUGAAAACUAUACCAGACUGCAUUUUGAAUGACGACUUUGUACCCAGUAUCUUCACAUGAGUUACUCUUUUGAUCCUCACAAGCCUCCAGAAGAGGUAGGUGAUGUCUUCUUGGUUUUACUAAGACAGGCAUCCAGGGCAUAGUUGGAGCCAGCAAGGGGCAGAGCAAGUCCUUGAACCCCGAUUGGUUUGACUUUAAAUUUUGUGUUCUUUCCUCUACAUCACAGCUGCUUGGAAGAGAACUGCCAGAUGCUGCUGUUAAUCAAGGUUGUGAAGUUGCAUACAAAUUGAGAAGGAAAGGAGGAGGAAACAGCAUCAUAAAUUUUGGCACAAAAGUGUAAAGCUUUUAAAGACCCUCAAUAUGUCACUGCUCCUAGCUAAGUUUGUUGCCACAUAAUUAGGCCGAAAGUCCUAAUUGCAGGUUGAUUUUUAAACCUACAUGACCCUGUGCCAGCAGGAUUUAUGCUGAGACAUUUACUUUAAUUAAAUGGCUACUUAGUGACAGGGCUUAAAUAUAUAUCAUUUAAAGAGCCAGAUAGUUUUUUUUCAGAUACUCGGUCGAUCAAGAACACAUUUCAUCCUUAUUAACAAUACAUAGUAUUCAACUAGAAAUAUUUGAUUUGAUUUCAUUUAAUUGAAGCCAUUUGAGGUCAUCAAAAAUUAUUUGCGGAGAUUUUCUCUAAUCUGUGGUUUCAGGGAUGGGAAAAUUGGAAACACAUGGAUUUACUACCUCACACUCUCCCACUUCAAAUGUUACACUGAGGCAUUGGUACCUUCUAACCCCCUGCACUGAGAGAACCUCAUGCGGCCAAAACCUUUGGUUUCUGAAGCCUAGCCAAUGACAUGCAAAAUAGCCUUUUCUCUACCAAAAGCAAGAAAAAUCUUCAGUUGAAAAAUUGGGCUAAUGUUGUUCAGUAAACAGUAUGAAUUAAAACUAGUUCAAUUUGGCUUAGAUUUUAUACAUCAUCUCAACACAGAAGAUUCUGAUGCAAAGUGAAAAAUGAAGCAUAUACUUGCUUUAAAAAUACAGCUGUUCUGGCCUGGCAUGGUGGCUGACUCCUGUAAUCCCAGCACUUUGGGAGGCUGAGCCGGGAGGAUCAUGUGAGGCCAGGAGUUCGAGACCAGCCUGGCCAACAUGGCAAAACCCUGUCUCUACUAAAAAUACAAAUACUAGCCAGGUAUGGUGGUGUGCGUAUAAUCCCAGCUACUCGGGAGGCUGAGGCAUGAGAAUCACUUGAACCCUGGAGGCAGAGGUUGUAGUGAGUGGAAAUUGUGCCACUGCAUUCUAGCCUGGGUGACAGAGUGAGACUCUGUCUCAAAAAAAACAAAACAAAAACAAAAAAAUCCAGCUGUUCUUCUAGUCCCAGAAUUCCAGUUUGGCCUGCCUUGGAGCAUCUAUUUGGGAACAGGCAUAUGUGACCUUCCAAUUCAAGACUUUGCUUCUGUUGUUGCUGCUGGGAUUGGCAGGCUUCUGUGUUCUAAUUACUCUUUUAAAAUUCCAUUUAAAAUGCAAUUUCAUGUAAAUGUGUGUUUUCACAUUUAGUUUUUAUAGCAUUUCUUUUCUUUCCCAACUAUAUCAGUGAUAGGUAUUAACUGUAAGAUGUGGUAUAUACAGAUGAGCAAAAGAAAAAAGGAGAAAAUAACUUGUAAUCUAAUCACUAAGACAUAAAUACUACUGACUUGGUCUUUUUUCUCUUACUCUUCCUCUUUAUGUAUGUAUGUACAUAUUUACUUAAAAUAUAGACUUGCUAUCUCAUUGUAUAUGUUACUUAAUGCAACAAAAUUCUUUUUGCAUGUUUGCCAGGUGCCAGACACUAGGCUAGGCCUUGGAUAUAGUUUUGUUUACUGUUUUUUUUAAAUUGUCACUUAAUGCUAUAUGAUAAAUAUUUCUCCAAGUCUUUAAAAAUUAUUUGAAAUGACAUUUUUAAUAGCUGCAUAAUAUCCCAUCAUUUUGAUGUGCCAUAUUUUAUUAUGUCCCUGAGAUUGGACAAUUAAGAAGCUUUUGGUUUUUUUUCUAUAAUAACCAACACCCUAAUAUACACCCUGAACAUAAAUCUUUGUGCUCAUCUCUGAUCAUUUCCUUAUAGUAAUUUCCCACAAAAAUUAUGGGGGUAAAGAAUAUGAAAAUAGCUAUAGCUUAUCUGAGGUUGCUUUUCAGUUGCUACCUUCAUCUUAUUCUUUCUUUGUCUCCAAAGUGACUUGAUUGCCUUAAAGUGAUUCUAAAAUUCACAUAGCAUUAGAGAAACCUAGACUAUGCUUUAGAAAACAGUCUAUCUUCCCAAAGAUACAUAUACCCUCUUAAAGGUGCUGUAGUAUUGCCAAGAUACAUACACAUAUAAUAUCUUAAAGUUGCUGUAUGUACCUUUUUAAAAAGAGAAAGAGUUCUAAGCUUGUUUACUUAGAAGGUCUAAUAAAUCAGAUCAUUAAAAGUGUGAGAAUUGCCUGUUUAUGAAAACGUGCAGUUGGUUCAAACUGGCUAUAUAAAUCGGCCAGAUUGUAUGAGCCAGUCUACAGGAGCUUAGCAGUGUACAGGUCCAAUUCCAUUAUUUGCUCAAUAAUAGUUUUAUGCUUAGGCUCAGCGUAUGAGGCUGAUAAUUGUGGCAUGAUAAGACUGCACAGUGCUCAAGUGUAUAAUGAGCAAUGCUUAGCUGGAAGAGAGAAAAUAUUUAUCAGUGCUUUGCUAAUGAGAUGUUUUUUAUAUCAUCUAAUGAGUUGGUUUUAUUUUAGGUAAGGUUAAAUGUGUUUAAUAUGUUUCAUAGAGAUCUUGAAAUAACAUGUGCUGAAAUAAAUUAGAAAAAAAAUCAGAAAAAUUCCAAGUGGGCUCUCUGGAGUAAUCACCUCGUAGAUAUUAUUUUGAAAACCAGAAAACUGGUUGGAAGAUGAUAUGCCAAAAAUAACAUUGUCUACAUUAAACAGACUUACUUUAUAGACCGCUUGUGUAACAAGAUGUAUAAUGCUCUCCUUUGAGAACUUCUCCUUCCUUCAGGCUAACCUUGUUUGGGUGAUAUACCAGACUGUGUUAGAGGGGUCAUAGCUCGCUGGGUGGCUAAGCCCCUAUAUGUGUGAGGUAGAAGUCUUGUAGAGUCAAAAUUACUCUUGAAAAUCUCUUUGGAAGGUGCCACCAUGGAGGCCUGUAUACUAUCCCUUGUGGAGGCCAACACAGCCACUUUGGCCUGCAGAGUUGGAGCCGCAUUGCUGUUUCUUUGAGCACCAGAUAAGAAGUUGGCUUGCAUUUAGGGGCCAACUUGUAUGAAAAAUAUGUUUCUUUAAACACUAGAAUCCCAGUCAGCUCUGUGAGAUGUUCACACUGUGAAAAGCUUUCUGGAAUGAGAUGCAGAGGAAGCUGUGGGGUCGUGUUUCCUUUUUUCUCUCUCACCGUGGGCAUGUGAUCACCGAGUUCCUGAUUGAAGUGUGUGUUUGUGUGUGUACGUGUCCACCUCCCUUCCUUGUGGGUGUUAACUGAAUUCUUUUGAGCAAAAACAUGUCUGACAUGACACCACUGCAGUUGCUGUGAUGCAGAAUUUUUACUCAUGUAGAAGUUCUUCUGUGAGAGCCUGCAAUAACCUUUUUGGUUAAUACUCCCUAUAAAAGGAGAGUGGAAGAGGCAGGGUGAACAAAUGUGUUAUUUUGAAUGAAUGUGAAUGAAUCAUGAGCAGAGAUUUAUUGAGGGCCUACUAUGUGCUAGCAGUUAGGGAUAUAGUGGUGACCACAGUGACCGAAUCCCUGCCCUUCUAAAACUUAUGGUCUUGGUAGAUUCCUGAGAAUUUGCCUUUGUCUAGGCAACAAUGGACUGACUAGAUAACCAUUAAAUACAUAGGGGUUCAAAUAUUUAGUGCAGAAGCAUUUUGGGUUCUCGAAUAGGGACUGUGUGAUACAAGUGGUUUCUUUGAAAAUUAUCCAUGAUCUAAGCUCACACACUUACUGGCUCAUAAAAGCCAGUUUCAGAGGCCAGAUGACUUUCGUGUUUGGUGCCAGUGUGCUCCCACUGGAUCCCUAUCUGCCUGGUUGCAAACUCUUGGCUCUAGUACUGCCUGAUCUCUAGCAUACUUUGAUCCACCAGAAAGUCCCUCCUUGUUCCAGUUCCAAAACUCUAGCUCUGCAAUAUCUCCUCUCCUUCCCCCAAAGUGGUGCUGUGGGGUGUGUGUGUGUGUGUGUGUGUGAGAGAGAGAGAGACUGAGAGAGAGAGAGAGGCUCAGUGAAGGGAAUUCCCGUGCAUGAGCUUACUGUUGAUUACUAGCCCUUCAUCACCGGAGUGUUGGUCACAAACCUGAGGAGGGCAAAGUGAUUGGAGUCCCGAGGUGCUUGUGUUCCUUUGGCUCUGUUGGUCUGGAUCUGUCGAUCACCUUUCUUGGGGCUUCUUUGUGCUGCGUCGUCUCCUGCUUGCUGCCCCCCACUAUUCCUCUUCUCUGAGUUAUGGUUUAUAACCUGCUGCAUCUCCUAAUGAACACCUGGAACCUCCAAGUUGGGAAAAGAAGGAGCAUCUCAUGGUGCCUGGGGCAGCAGGAUGGUGUGGCCCUGACUUGGCCCAAGAUUCUUGUGCCCCUCGAGGUGGUACCCCUGAGAAAUGUACUCAUGGGAUUAGCGUGAUUUCACAGAUGGUUAAUUUUUUUAAGUUAGUUAACUAAAGACAUUAUUUUUCCAUUGAAAUGAACAUGGAUAUCUUAAGGCAGCACUAGACUGUAAAAUUCAUGUGAAUGUUAAGUUAAAAACGUAUUUUUCAGGCAGACAUGUAGGGAAAGACGUUCACUCUUGUCUUCUGUUACAGGUACUUUGGUGGAAGUACCUGGUUGAUCCUGGCUCCUUGGCUAAGUUAUUGAAAUUUUCUGCAGAAUGGGGAUAGUUGGAGGAUUCACUGGGAUAUGCAGAAAACACUGAGUGUGUGUUACUUGCCAUCUCUUCCUGCUCCCCAUUUCCCCACAACAUCCCUGGGUUGUCUCUCACCCUGGAGGUAUCCUGCUCCCUGUGUCACUGCUUCUGUGGCAGGAACUAUGCCUUCCCUGCCCACGUGUGCUGGUGAUGCUGCUCCUGGGUGUCCUUGGAUCUGCCCAAAGGGCAACUCCUGUGAUCUCCCAGAAUAUUGAGGGUGCAGGACCAAGGAGUCCUUAGAGAGCAGCUGCAGCCUAGGUCAUGGCAUAGGGGUGGGUGGGAUAUGAUUAGAGAAGAGGCAGGGGGUCCUCCUGGCCCGCUGCCUUUUCUCGGCAUGCAGGUGCACAGUGGCGUCUACAUACUAUGAGGGAGUGUGUGAUCCCCAGGUAAACCCCACUGAUGGAGCAGGACAGGACUAGCUUCUAGACACCCCCUCUCCAAUACCACCAAACAGAGCACAUCCUGCCCCACAUGGAUGCCUCUGCCCCAUCAAAGGUGGCAGGAGGACAUUUGCCUCUCCAGCCUCUCAUUCACUGUGCUCAGUUUCUGUUUCUGACCCCCUUUGAAGCUGCCUCUCUCCAUAAGGGAGGAAUGAUAUCUGAGCCGAAGGAGGAUGACACAUGCCAUUCCAGUCCACAACCCGUGGCCCCCUAAUCUCUCCAAGACAAGAUGUUCCAACAGGUGGGGGUGAUCCUUCUCUCUUAAGGCCUGCCUUGCAUGAGGACAAUUUGCUUCCUUCCUAAUCUCUGGAAGAAGGUGUUAGAGUCAGAUAGGCAUUGGCCUUAAGGAACAUUUAUUUCUGAGUGUACCAAGUGUGUCUUUGAUGCUUUCCCAGAGGAACCAGCUCAGUGUAAUGGGAACAGAACAAGCUUUGGCGUCAGAGAAAUCUUGGUCUGGAUGGGACCUCAGCCCCUCACUAGCUUUAUAACAUCAGUCAGGUUACUUACAUUACUGAGCCUUGGUUUUCUCAUCUGUAAACGGAAGAUGUUAAUCGUAACUCACUGUUAGGGGUGAAGAGGAAGCAAUAUAAUGUAUGAAAAGUGCUUGCCAUACAGUAGUAGCUCAAUAAGUGCUUCUCAACACAUCUCAAGCCCAGCAUUGGAUUCAAGACAGUCCUUCUUAGGAGGCCUCAAAUCACAUUUGUUUUCUUUCUUUGUCUCCAUUCGAAACACCCAACUUCCUCUUGCUGCUGUUCUUUUUUUAGGAGUCAAGAAAAAACAACCUAAGUAAACAUUCUCCACUAAGGUGUGACUGAAAGAUAGUCUCCUCACUCACUCAGAGGUGAUUUCAACAGGGGAAACUUUAACUCAAAGGAAUUUCUGUAAGACGUCUCUUAGGUAGUAGGAGUGGAUUCCUGUGGUCUCUGUGCGGUUCCUGGCUUUGCCCAUAUUCCCCCAAGUGAGGUCUCCAAGUACCCAGUCCCCAGCAGCCCUCAACUUCUAGCCGCAGUCAUAUCUUCACUCCCUGUUAGGCUAAACCCUCAUCUGAUUCUUUGCUCCCCUGACUCACAAGACAAUCUUGUGCUGUGUGCUGAUACAGCAUGCUUAUCUGUCCAUCUUAGAGAACUUAGAAGCAAUGUGCUUUAGCUUUUCAUGACAAUUUCCAUAAACUAUCCUAGUUCUUAGAGGAAAAUGAAGUAGUUAAAUGAAAGACCAAUCAACCAAUGUUUAAUUCUUGAUGAAAUUAAAAGUUAACUGAUGACAUAACUGGUGGAUCAUCCAGAUUUCUCCUAAACUGGAACGGCAAAUGGGCCAGCUGUUAUUGACUGGUAAUGAUUGCCUGGACUGCUUGAGUGCUGAGGAAGAGUCUAAGGUUGUGCUUAUUCAAGAUGGAAAAGAGUAUCAUGCUUGAUUAGUGAUGUCUGCUAAAGGCACAGGAAUGGAUGUGGCAGCUCUGACUACAUAUUUGUCAGGCCUUUCUCCGACUCCCAUCCCACCAUUUCUCUGUUCAUUUGCACUCCCACUUGAGAGCAGUUGGGGAAUUGAAAGUGUUUUCAAGCCAGGUUUACUCUGGUAAAUGAUUUAGCAGGGCUGAAGCAGGAUGCCAACUAAAACUUGUUUUUCAUGAUUAUCUAUAGAUUUUAUAUUUAUCCUAUUCUUGGUGUACAUUCACAUAAUUAAGAGUUGCUAUGAAGUCAGAGUUUUUUUAUCUCAAGGCUCAUAAACAGCAUCAGGAUUUGGUCUAUUCGAAGAAACUACUCAGAACGUCUUGUCUUUUCAUCUCUGAACAGCCAUGAGAAUGUGAACUGUAGGCAAGGAAAUGAAUUGCAUUCAUGAAUCACUUGAGCGGCACAAAGCAAAGCUUAGAGCUACCUCUAAUAGUCUUGCCUGUUAUAUCCCCUUUGCCUUUAUUCUAAAUGCCUAUUUUCCAGAUAGCCUAAUGGAUGAAUCACACUAUGUUCUGAGAGAGGCAGACAAAUAGCCUGGAGAAAAUGGGGCACUUACAUGGGAUUUCAGGUUAUUCUUCUCCAAGCUUACCAUUAGAACCCAUGUGAAAGCAUUAAAGAGAAAGCUAUUCUUUUUUUUAUUUUUUAUUUUUUAUUUUUUUGAGACAGAGUCUCGCUCUGUCGCCCAGCCUGCAGUGCAGUGGUACAAUCUCGGCUCACUGCAAGCUCUGCCUCCCAGGUUCACACCAUUCUCCUGCCUCAGCCUCCCGAGUAGCUGGGACUAUAGGCGCCCACCACCACGCUCGGCUAAUUUUUUGUAUUUUUAGUAGAGACGGGGUUUCACCAUGUUAGCCAGAAUGGUCUCAAUCUCCUGACCUCGUGAUCUGCCCUCCUCGGCCUCCCAAAGUGCUGGGAUUGGGAUUACAGGUGUGAGCCACACUGCUUCUGGCCAAGAAAGCUAUUCUUGAAAAAUAAGAUACCUGGUGUGUGGCACAGCUUACCAUUGCCCACUUACCUCUCUCACUGGGAACUGAACCACCUGGAUAUUAGAAGUUGAAGGGCUAAUUGCUCUUUCUAGAAGUUUUGCUUAUUAUCUUCCAUUCUUCCCUUAAGGUGGAAGGAGAGGUGAGUGGAUCAUCAUAUAAGCCUUCUGAGAACUAAGAAGAAACUACCAGCCCCUUCUCUGGCCUCCACUUUGUUCUUGCACUAUUGGGGCGCGUGGGGGUUGUCACCUGGUAUCAAGCAUUCUCCACUAGGGCACCUAUAGGCAGGUUGAGGUCACGCUUUUGUUUUGAGAGUCUUCUGUGGAGUUACUUAGAAGAUGUCUAAAAUACGUAACAAAUCUCAGACCUCUCUUUGAGCAUUGACAGUAACAUAUUUAGAAAGUUCGAGGAAAGUGAUUUUUUAAAAGUUCAUCAAUACUAUGUAAUACUACGAUAAAACCAACAGCCCAAUAAUAGCAACAAAACUCCCUGUCACCAUUUGGUGUCGCCUCUUCUUUCCUGGCUGUACAAUUUAUAGAAGGGGGAGGAAGACUUUAGAAUUUUACUUUUAGGAAUCCAGUACAUUUUUAAAAAGCUGGUUGUGUUAGAGGCUGGCUUGUAAGAACUCGUAUGUGUCUUCCUCAUUUCUGUUUUUCUUUGAGUUGCCAAAUGUUAAGGUUGGGAUUAUUCAACCCAUAUGGGGCAUGAUUUCCUUUUUUCUAUAACAUUUCUGGGCAAGCAGAUUUUGACUCAGUGCUACCAAUCUGGGGUGUGUGCUCCCUUUUCCUGGUGGACUGGGGAAAGGUCUAUCAUAAUCUCAUGAAAGAGCACCAUGGCAAAGGAAGAAACGAGAAGAGGAUCUUUCUCAGUGAUUUGAGAUCAGUGGUGAGCUGGUGUUAAGAGUAGUGUUUCAAGAGAAAAACAGAAAGGGAAGGGAACAUUUUCAUUUUCUAAUAUAUGUUUUUCUCUGCUGGCCUUUGAGAUGCCAGAAUGAUAAAAAUCAGAGGGGUCAUCUGAGAGGUGGCAAAAAAUAAAAAUCACCUCUAAAAGAGAAGCAGCUUAAUGUGCCAUCCGCAGGCACAGCUGUUUAAUCAUGGGUGAUUAUUACACUGGGAUAGACUAAAAGAAUUAAAAGAAUGUUGUGGCUGUGAUUUAAACAAUGAGGACUCUGGUAAGAACGUCCUGGCCUCAUUGGUGAACUAGGACUGCAACCUGAAUGGAGUUAUUGAAUAAAUUGAUAGCACAGUUUUCAGACACCUGCCCCCUUCCCUCCAUGCCAUGAUUUUCCAGUUGCUUGCUCUGUGGCCAAUUUUGGGGUAGAUCCAAACUUGCUUCUUCAGCACCUAGCAACAAUCUCAAAUGCCACAAGAAGAGUUUUAAUUUAAUUUAGUGCACGGCCACAUUUAGUAAGUUUUUGAGAAUGUUCCUAAUUUAUUAGCUUAAAAUCUUAUCACGAUUUUUAAAUCCAUCACUUCUCUUCAAAGAAUGAUGAAUUAAAAUGUAGGUAAAUUUUUCUUACUUUCCUUGAAUGAAAUACACUGAGAGCAGACAGUCUGAUUGACACUGUUAUGUAUGAACAUGAGGGACGUAAUUCUAAAGAGUACUGGCCUUGCAAUAACUCUUUAGAUUUAUCUUAUGUGACUCCUAUGCUUAAUGACUCUUUGACAAUUGAUGAUGGAGGAGCCAGUCCUGUACAUCCUUUCCCUACUAUGUUAUUAUUGAUAACAUAAUCAACCAAAAUGCUUUUUGUUUGUUUGUUUUGAGACGGAGGAGUCUCGCUCUGUCGCUCAGGCUGGAGUGUAGUGGCGCCAUGUCGGCUCACUGCAAUCUCUGCCUCCCAGGUUCAAGCCAUUCUCCUACCUCUGCCUCCCAGGUUCAAGCCAUUCUCCUACCUCAGCCUCCCGAGUAGCUGGGAUUACAGGCGUGUGCCACCAUGCCUGGCCGAUUUUUGUAUUUUUAGUAGAGAUGGGUUUUGCCAUAUUGGCCAGGCUGGUCUCAAACUCCUGACCUCAGGUGAUCCGCCCACCUCUACCUCCCAAAGUGCUGGGAUUACAGGCACGAGCCACUACGCCUUGCCUUAUUUAAUACUUUUGAAAUUACUUCCCUAAACAUCUUUUCCCUAGCAGAGCGCUAACAGUGUGAACUUCACGGCAGCAGAGACUAUGUUUGUUUUCACCCAUGCUUGUAUGUCCAGCCUAGGCAGAAUGGCCAGCACAUAAGAAGGGCUCUGUAAUAUUAUUUACUGAAAGAAUGAGUGAAAAAACAUCAUCUCUAUGCUGCACAUCUUCUGUCGUGCCACCACUUUUGUGUGGCUUGUCAUCCCCUCUUAGCUGAAUGACUGCCACAGCCUCCCUUGUGUUCUCUCCGCCAAUCCAUUCUCCUCUCCGCAGCCAGUCUGAGCUACUAAAAUGUGCAUCUGCAUAUGUCACCCCCUUCUGUUCAGUCUUACUUGCUUCCUGUUUCUCUGAGGUUAGUGACAAAGUCUCAGCGUGGCCAGCCCCACCUUACAAUUUCACUCCUUGCAUCCCACACUCCAGCCUCUGAACUAGUCACAUUUCCCCACACCUGGUAGGCUUAGGCUCCCUCUGAUCUUUGGGUCUCUGUAGAUGUUACACCUUCACCUAGGAAUCUCUUUUCCCCAGCUUAGCUGUCACCUCCUCUCUGAAGCCUUCCCUGAUGACACAAGGCUGGGUUGGGUGUCCCUCCCAUAUGACCCUGUUGCUUCCACCGUGAUGUCACUGUUUACUUUUCUUCCUCCUCUCUAGAUUCGAAGCUUCUUGAGCCUGGGACUGUAUCUUGAUCAUUGCAGAAUCCUUGCCACCUAAUGCAUUGCCUGGCCCACCAUCGGCACUUGGAGAAAUGAUUGUUGAGUGGGCAAGAAGAGGGCAAUAUGGCAUAGUUGAACUAGCAUGGGAUCUGGAGCUGGAAAGAUCUUCCCAGUGACUGGCAGUCACCUUGGGCCAUCCCCAAACUCCCCAAGCCCCAGUUUCUUUCUCAGGGAAAUGGGGUGGAGGACAUCACUUCGCAACUCACCAGGUUGUUCUGAAAAAUACAGUGAGAUGACAUAAGGAAAGCAGCACAGGGCCUGCUCCAUAAUGAGCUCUGGUACAUUGUUCUUCCUUUCCUCAAUCCCUCCUUCCCUUCCUUACUGGCCAGGUGGGUAAAACCAUGGAUCAGAAUACUAGAAUUCCAGUGUUACAGUCAAAGAUUAAGUGGUUCUAAAUCAUCUAGAACCAGAAAUAACAUUUGACCCAGCAAUACUAUUACUGGGUAUAUACCCAAAGGGGAUGCUUUUUAAAAAUACACACUCCUGGACCUUACUCUGUGGUUCUGGGACAGGGUCCAGGAGUCUGUAUGCUUUGUUUCAAGUUUCUAAUGUGCAGCCACAAUUGGGAGCUUUUGACCUAGUCCAACUUCUGACCCAAAGCAGGAAUCCUGGUUAUGUAGCCUUUGCUGGAGCACAUCAGGGAUGGGCAGCUCGCUGCAUUUUGAAGCUGUUUCUUGCUGGACAGCUGCUCUAAUAGAGACCUCUCCCUUAUAGACUGUGCCCCAUUCUGCUUCUCUGAUAACACCCAGCCUUUAGAUCGGGUUCUGCCUUCUAGAGACACAUGAAUUAACCUACACCAUCUUCCACAUAGUCAUUUUUCAGAUACUUGAUGUUACUAGUACUAUAUCCCUUCAAAGGUUUUUCUUUUCCAGCCUAAACAUUCCUGUUCUUAUAAACUAGAAUUUGCUAACUGGAGCCUGCGGGCUACAUCCGGUCCACAGAUGUGUUUUGUUUGGCCUGUGGUGUUUGAAAAAUAUUGAAUAAGUUGCCAACAUUUAAAAAUCAGGGCAUUUCACUGAAACGUCUGGAGCUCUGGCAUCUCUUGAAAACUCAAAAGAUCUGGAGCCACAAUUUUAUCUUUGGACAGGACAUAAAUUCUCCAGAUUGUUGCAGCCUUCACCACUCUAUGCUCUUGUCUAGCCCCCUACCUGAAUCAUUAUGUCACAUGUUUCCAGACCCUUCGUUAUUCUCAUUUUCUUUUCCUAGCUGUGAUGCAAAGUGUCAGUGGUCCCAUCUUUAAAGAAAAUUUUUCUUUUUAUGUUUACAAAAAUGAUAGUUAACAAUAAUAAUAAACAUAAUAUUAUAGAAAAUUUGGAAAUUACAAAAAAAGAAAGUGUAUCUGCCAAUAACCCUGUUUAGCAUUUUUAUAAAUUUUCUUCUAGUCCUUGUUUUUCUGUGCAUAUUUAUAUGCUAUGAAGCUGAGAUCAAACUGUAUAUAGUUUCAUAGACUGCUUUUUUUCCACAUUUUCCUCAUCUCAUUAAACUCCCUCAAAAGGCCAAUUUUAAUAAGUAAAAUAUUCUGUUUUAUGUAUCAUAAUUUUUUUUAUUGUGGCAAAAUACACCUAACAUGAUAUUUACCAUUUUAACCAUUUUAAAAGGUACAUUCACAGUGUUGUGCAGCCAUUAUUACUAAUUCCAGAACAUUUUCACCACCCCAAAUGAAACUCUGUAUCCAUGAAGCAGUCACUUCCCGUUCCCUCCCGAUCCCUGGUAACUGCUAAUCAGCUUUCUGUUUCUAUGUGUGGCUAUUUCAUAUAAAUGGAAUCAUACAGCCUGUGGCCUUUUGUGUCUGGCUUCUUGCACUUAGCAUAAUGUUUCCAAGGUUCAUCCAUGUUGUAGCAUCUAUCAUUAUACGCUGUUCCUUUUCAUGGCUGAGUAAUAUUUUACUCUACGGCUGUACCACAUUUGGUUUAUCCAUUCAUCAGUUGAUGCCGGUUGGUGGACACUUGGGUUGUUUCUACCUUUUGACUGUUGUGAAUAGUACUGCUGUGGACAUUUAGGUACACGUUUUUGCUUCAACACCUAUUUUCAGUUCUUUGGGAUAUACACAUAGCAGUGGAAUUUCUGAAUUAUAUGGUAAUUCCAUGUUUAACUUAUUGAGGAACUACCAAGCUAAAUAGCUAAAUAAAAUUCCACAGCAGCUGCACUAUUAUACAUUCCAAUCAGCAAUGUUCCAAUUUCUUCACAUUCUUCCCAACACUGUUUUCUGGGUUUCGUUUGUUUGUUUUGUUUUAGCCAUCUAGUGUGUGUGAAAUGGUAUCUCACACACACCAGAAAUGGUGAAGUAGUUCUUAGAGAUUUAUAUUCUCUAAAGACUGAUGUUAAGCAUCUUUUCAUGUGCUUUUUGGCCAUUUGUAUAUCUUUUUUGGUUUAUAUAUUAUAACUUGCUCAAUAAUUUCCCUAGCUUUGACAUUGGUUCCCUUUUAAUUUUUCCUGUCAUAAAUAGUGUUGUUAUGAACAUCUUUAUACAAAAAUUGUCUGUAUAUCUCAUUAUUUCUAUAGGACAGCCUCCCUGAAGAGGGACUGUGGGGUCAAAGGAGUAGGAUUUCGAAGGUAUUGAGAUGAAGAAUCAGAUUCAGUGCUGCAUGUAUGUUGAAGCUGUAUGAGUCACCUGGAGAGCCUUUGCAAGCGCUUGUGCUAGGAUUUGCAUCCCUAACACUACCUCAGGCUUAUUGGGGUGGGACCUAGUUUCCCAGGGGAUUUUGAUAUGCAAUCCAGCCAAAAAACAUCAGCCAAAUUUCUUCUGCAUCCAUUUAGGUCUUAAAAAAAAAAAAGGCCAGGCGUGGUGGCUCACACCUGUAAUCCCAGCACUUUAGGAGGCUAAGGCGGGUGGAUCACUUGAGCCCAGGAGUUCAAGACCAGCCUGUCCAACAUGACGAGACCCCCUCUCUACAAAAAUUUUUUAGAAAAAUUAGCUGGGUGUGGUGGUGCACACCUGUAGUCCCAGCUAUUUGGGAGGCUGAUGGGGGAGGCUCACCUGACCCCAGGGAGGUCGAGCUUGCAGUGAACUGUGGUUAUGCCACUGCACUCCAGCCUGGGGGACAGAGCAAGACCCUAUCUUAAAACAAACAAAAAACAAAAAAGAGGCCUGUAAGAUCUGCACGAAAUUGUCCACUACUCUGACCAGUUCUGAGCAGCUUGGUCCUGCUACUUCCCCUGCUGUGUGCAUCAAGCUUGGUCGUCUAGCUCUUCUGGCAGAGUGAGAUUAUAGUCACCUAGACCACCCCUUAUUGGGUUUUUUUUUUUUCCAUCUGAAAUCUCAUCUUUUCCCUUAUUGUUCUUGGAGGAGUCGAUCAUUUUGGACCUAUCUUUUCUGGUAAGAAAACAGAGGUUUCUGCCUGCUCUGUGACUUGCCCUCCGUUAUGUAACACCUACUGAUCAAGGGUAGACCAGGACUCCUGGCGCAUCAGUUAAUUUCUUUCCACUCCCUUCAAUGGCCUUGUUUCAUCAUUUUUGAUUGGUCACAAUUCAAGAAGCAAAAAGUUGCUGCACAGUGCCAAAUGUACCAAGUACUCUAAAAGUGAGAGCAAGCCUCUGCGUGCCUGGGCAGGCCACUGCUGUCACAGGCCACCUGCCUUUCACCAAGUCCACUUCUAUCCCUGGGUGGAGGAGGGGCAGCUAAAAGUUCUCCUUUGUCAGGACAGUCAACCAUGAUCUCAAAAGAACUAUGAUUGUAUUGUGCAUUUUAAACCCUUGGAAUGUUACAUGGUGAUGAGGUAACAGUGGCUAUGAAUGUUCUUACAAGUGGGAGCUGAGCAUUGGGUACACAAGGACACAAAGAUGGGAAUAGUAAACACUGUGAAUCCCAAAAGGGGGCAGGAUGGGAGGAGGGCAAGAGAUUAAAAACUACCUAUGGGGCACUAUGUUCACUACUUGGGCGAUGGGAUCAUUAGAAGCCCAAACCUUAGCAUCACACAGUAUACCUGUGUAACAAACCUGCACAUGUAUCCCCUGCAUCUGAAAUAAAAACACAAAACACAAAAACAAAAUAUAAAAACAACAGCUCUGAGUUUUGACAUAAGGUGUGCAGUGCAGAUUCCCAAAUCUAGAUUUAACAUGCGACGACACUAACAGGGUCUCCACAUCAUUCAGAGCCAACGUCAGGGGGAUUGUUGGUGAGGAGAGGGGAGUGUGGAUACCAGGAAAGGAACCAACCUCAGUUAUGUCAGUUGGGCCAGAGGAGGCCAAAGGAUCCUAUCUCCCUGAUGCCUUGUCUCAGACCUCAGUUGCCUUUGUGGUUGCCUAGUGCCACGGAGGCAACGGGCAUUCAAAAUUCUGCUAAAUAAAAACACACAGCAAAUUAGGUUUUAUUUAAACUCAGUAACUUACUCUCCUUGUUAAAAACUCAGUAACUCACUCCCUUAUUUUCUGUAAUAUGACUGUCAAGAUUAUGUCUUCACACGUGCCCUUCACAUGAACAUUCUGGGAGUGCAUCUUGUUUUCCUAAUGUUUAAAAAACAUGCUGCAAGCUAAUUUUAAACUGGGAUGGGUAAUGAAAAAGAGAGAAUCAUAGACUUCUCUGUGGCACCACCUCUCAGUUAAAAAUUACCCAUGCCUUUUUAAUCUCUAGUCUUUGAGACUAAAAGCACAUUAAUCUACUUAUUCCUAAUUCAUUUUCAGAAUUUUCCCAUAGAGCUACUUAUAUUCAGUCUCAAGGCAUACUAUAUAUCAGGACAUACACUAAACUUUCAAAUCAUAUUUAACAAUUGAUAAAAUUUAAAACUUGUUAUUAAAUAUUUUCAUUUAAAUGGAUUUGGAGAAGUUGCAAACAUACUAUUGCAACAUAGAGUGAAAGACCAACACUGUAGUGACUGUCGAUGUAAACAUUUUAACAAAGUUUUUGAUUAUCAAAAGAACUGAGGUCUUUUUGGUUGCUAAAUUCCAGUCACUUCAUUAUUGCUUUCUUUCAUGUUAUUCAUAUUAUUUUCCAGAUGGGCAGGAGCAGCUUAAAUGACUACUGUUGUUUGAAGGGCACAGCAAGCGUUGUAUGUGUUUUGGCAGGGGGUAGCAUAGGGCAUGAGAAGGACAGGGAAGGAAGAGAUUUGGAGGUAAUUUCAAGCUCGUGCUGUCUGGAAGUAGUGCAUUUUAAAUUAGUGUUAGUGUGAUGUUCUGCAGCAGCCAAGCUUGGGAAUUUUUUAUAUCUUUAAGCAGAGUCUGGCGAGUGGUGGUGGUGGGAGGAGUAUGAGAAGAGGGUGUUUAGAAAUGCUGUAACUCAGGACAUUCUCCUGAGCAUAUACAUGUCUAAAGUCAGUGCUGUGCCCUGCCUCAUUUGUCAUUCCAAAAUACAUUUUUUUCCUUCCUCCAUCUAAACCAUGUUCAGGCCUUGUUCAAGUCCUGCCUCCUCCAGAGACACCACUCUGGCUUCUUAGCCUUUCAUGCUUCCCCUUUUCUGAAUCAAGAAGGCUCCUAGAAUAUUAUGGCUAAAGGCACCUCCAGAUUACCUCUCCAAUCUGUCAUUGUGCAGAAGGACAACUUGGCAUCCAUUUGCAUGAGGUCUGUAGAACAUGGUUCAGUACUGUCUUACACAGUUUAAGUGUUUUGUGUGGGUUAGGCUUAUUUCCCCAACUAUAUUUGGCAGUCUUUUAGGAAAGGACUAUGUCACACAUUUCUUUUGUAUAUUUCAUAAAAAUAGCAUAUUGUAGGUACUCAGAAAAUGCUUUUGGCUCUGGUAGCACUUCUCUGUGCAAUGUGGAUAAGCACUGAUAGAGGCUUGUUUGUUGUGGUACAAACUAGAAACAACCCAAAUGCCCAUUCGAAGGGGAAUAAUUGAAUAUGUUAUGGCAUAUCCAUACAAUGGAAUAGUAUUAUAUAUAGUUAUUAAGAGAAAUGAUUUAAUCCUGUAGCUAUCGACCUGGGGGAUGUCCUCAGUACAUCAUUAUUUUUGCAAAUUGUAAGAGAGGGAAAUAAGCCAGGCAUGGUGGUAUGCAUCUGUAAUCCAGACUACUUGGAUUACAGAUACUUGGGUGGGAGGAUCGCUUGAACCCAAGAAUUUGAGACCACCCUGGACAAUAUAGCAAGACCCCCAUCUCAAAAAAAGUGUGUGUGUGGGAAAUAGUAAAAUCCCAUUUUCUGAUAAUAAAUAACGAUAAUCUCAUAUAUCUGUAUCUGUACCUACCAACAAGAACACGGGCUGUUCACAUUUGUGGUAGGAAAGGUUAUUAAGUUUUUUCUUUAUCUGUUUUUGUAUUGUUGCAACAGGAAACCUACUAAGAUUAAAAUCCAGCAAACAUAAGACAAAGAUAAAAUGCACAGGGGUUUUGAUGCAUUAGGUGUUUCCCAUAGUACUUCCUAUUUUUCAAACUUCGUGUGAUUAAAAAAGUAAGUUUUAUCCCUGACUAAAUUUCAGUGUGGAAAUAAAGAAAUAAAGAUAGCAUGUACUUGGCUUAGGUAUACUUGUUUUGUUCUUUCAGCUCGUUACGUAAAGAUACAUUUUUUUUUCUUUCUCAUGACAUGAAGAUAAGCUUUCUUCUUACCAAAACCUAAACUGUGAAGGCAGCACCCAAGCCAAAAGCCUCGAGGCUCUGGUUUCUGUGGUGGGAUGGGGAGAGAAGUAGGUUGCACAGAUGUAGGAUGCCAGCUGACUUCAGAACUUCCGGUCUCAGAGCUAACCAGGCUCGGCAAGCCACAAGAGAGAAGGAGCUUGCAUAGGUGGAAGAGCAAAGAAAGCCAGUGCUGCAGAACUUCCGGUGCUCCUCCGCCGAUGUCGGGCUGGCGCUGCUCCCGAGCCCUGUGUCCUGUGGAAGAAGUUGCCACCAUUGGUUCAGGCAAUCUUCAGCGGUGAUCCAGAGGAGAUCCGGAUGCUCAUCCAUAAAACUGAAGAUGUGAAUACUCUGGAUUCUGAGAAACGAACCCCUCUUCAUGUGGCCGCAUUUCUGGGAGAUGCAGAGAUCAUUGAACUCCUGAUUUUGUCAGGAGCUCGUGUAAAUGCCAAGGACAACAUGUGGCUGACUCCACUGCACCGGGCUGUUGCUUCCAGAAGUGAAGAAGCAGUACAGGUUUUGAUUAAGCACUCAGCUGAUGUCAAUGCAAGGGACAAGAACUGGCAGACCCCUCUUCAUGUGGCAGCAGCCAACAAGGCUGUCAAAUGUGCAGAAGUGAUCAUUCCCCUGCUGAGCAGUGUCAAUGUCUCCGACCGAGGGGGGCGCACAGCCUUGCACCAUGCGGCUCUGAACGGCCACGUGGAGAUGGUCAAUUUACUCUUGGCCAAAGGGGCAAAUAUCAAUGCAUUUGACAAGAAGGACCGGCGUGCUCUGCACUGGGCAGCAUACAUGGGCCACUUGGAUGUUGUAGCAUUGCUCAUUAACCAUGGCGCAGAAGUGACCUGUAAGGAUAAGAAGGGUUAUACCCCUCUGCAUGCUGCAGCCUCCAAUGGACAGAUUAAUGUUGUCAAGCAUCUCCUGAACCUGGGGGUGGAGAUUGAUGAAAUCAAUGUCUAUGGAAAUACAGCGCUUCACAUCGCCUGCUACAAUGGACAGGAUGCUGUGGUUAACGAGUUGAUUGACUACGGUGCUAACGUGAACCAGCCAAACAAUAAUGGGUUCACCCCUUUGCAUUUUGCUGCUGCCUCCACUCAUGGUGCUUUGUGUCUUGAAUUGUUAGUAAACAACGGGGCAGAUGUUAACAUUCAGAGUAAAGAUGGCAAAAGUCCACUGCACAUGACAGCUGUCCAUGGAAGGUUCACACGGUCACAGACCCUCAUUCAGAAUGGAGGUGAAAUUGACUGUGUGGAUAAGGACGGCAACACUCCUCUCCAUGUGGCUGCAAGAUACGGUCAUGAGCUUUUGAUUAACACCUUAAUAACCAGCGGAGCUGACACAGCCAAGUGUGGAAUCCAUAGCAUGUUCCCUUUACAUUUAGCUGCCCUAAAUGCUCACUCUGACUGCUGCAGAAAGUUGUUAUCAUCGGGACAAAAGUAUAGCAUAGUAUCCUUGUUUAGUAAUGAGCACGUGCUGUCUGCAGGCUUUGAAAUAGACACCCCAGAUAAAUUUGGAAGAACGUGCCUUCAUGCUGCUGCUGCAGGAGGUAAUGUGGAAUGUAUAAAACUCUUGCAGAGCAGCGGAGCAGAUUUCCAUAAAAAGGACAAGUGUGGGAGGACCCCUUUGCACUAUGCAGCUGCGAAUUGUCAUUUCCACUGUAUUGAGACAUUAGUGACCACAGGGGCCAACGUUAAUGAAACAGAUGACUGGGGACGCACAGCUUUGCAUUACGCCGCUGCAUCAGACAUGGAUAGAAAUAAGACUAUCUUAGGAAAUGCCCAUGAUAAUUCAGAAGAACUUGAAAGAGCCAGGGAGCUGAAGGAAAAGGAAGCCACACUAUGUCUAGAGUUUCUGCUUCAAAAUGAUGCAAAUCCAUCUAUCCGGGACAAGGAAGGUUACAAUAGCAUACAUUAUGCUGCCGCCUAUGGGCACAGGCAGUGUCUGGAAUUGCUUUUGGAAAGAACAAACAGUGGAUUUGAAGAAUCAGAUUCUGGUGCUACUAAGAGUCCACUCCACUUAGCUGCCUACAAUGGGCACCAUCAAGCCUUGGAAGUCCUUCUGCAGUCGUUGGUGGACCUGGACAUCAGGGAUGAGAAAGGCCGCACUGCUCUGGAUCUGGCUGCCUUUAAAGGACACACAGAAUGUGUGGAAGCGCUUAUCAAUCAGGGCGCAUCCAUCUUUGUGAAAGACAAUGUAACCAAAAGAACCCCACUUCAUGCCUCAGUAAUUAAUGGUCACACACUGUGUUUACGGCUGUUGCUAGAAAUUGCAGACAACCCGGAGGCGGUCGAUGUGAAAGAUGCCAAAGGACAAACACCACUGAUGCUUGCAGUAGCAUAUGGACAUAUUGACGCUGUUUCAUUGUUACUUGAAAAGGAAGCCAACGUAGACACUGUUGACAUCCUAGGAUGCACAGCUUUACACAGAGGGAUUAUGACAGGACACGAGGAAUGUGUGCAAAUGCUGCUGGAACAAGAAGUGUCAAUUCUCUGUAAAGAUUCCAGAGGGAGGACGCCCUUGCACUAUGCAGCUGCUCGUGGCCACGCCACGUGGCUGAGCGAGCUGCUCCAAAUGGCUCUUUCUGAGGAGGACUGUUGUUUCAAAGAUAACCAAGGCUACACGCCGCUGCACUGGGCUUGUUACAAUGGUAAUGAAAACUGUAUAGAGGUACUUUUGGAGCAAAAAUGUUUUCGCAAAUUUAUCGGUAAUCCCUUUACUCCACUGCACUGUGCAAUAAUCAAUGAUCAUGGGAAUUGUGCAUCAUUGCUGCUUGGGGCCAUAGAUUCCAGUAUCGUCAGUUGUAGAGAUGACAAAGGCAGGACACCCCUUCAUGCGGCAGCAUUUGCUGAUCAUGUGGAGUGCUUGCAGCUUCUUCUGAGACACAGUGCUCCAGUGAACGCAGUAGAUAAUUCAGGGAAAACAGCACUGAUGAUGGCUGCUGAGAAUGGGCAGGCAGGCGCUGUGGAUAUUUUGGUGAACAGUGCCCAGGCUGAUCUGACUGUAAAGGAUAAGGACUUGAAUACACCCUUACAUUUGGCUUGUAGUAAAGGUCAUGAAAAAUGUGCCUUGUUAAUACUUGACAAGAUACAAGACGAGAGCCUUAUUAAUGAAAAAAAUAAUGCACUGCAGACACCCCUCCACGUCGCUGCGCGCAAUGGCUUAAAGGUGGUAGUUGAGGAGUUGCUGGCCAAAGGGGCCUGUGUACUUGCUGUAGAUGAAAAUGGUCAUACCCCGGCCCUGGCUUGCGCUCCUAACAAAGACGUGGCUGACUGCCUGGCCCUCAUUUUGGCUACCAUGAUGCCUUUUUCUCCUUCCAGUACAAUGAUGGCUGUCAACUUCGUUUGUUUAAAAAAAGACAAUUUGAGCAGGACGACCCUCUCCAAUCUGGGUAGCAUGGUUAGCCUGUGCAGUAACAACGUAGGCUCGGAGGAUGGGUACAAUGAAAAUGAUUCUGAUUCGGAAACGUUUUGACUUUGGACUGUAGAAGCUUUUCUUUGAUCACCUGUGUUGGAGGAAAGGAAAGAAGCUUGAAUUCCAGGUUUAUGUUGUAUUCAAGUAUUAUUUGGGGCCUGGGCUUCCAGAAGCUAGUAGAGAAGGAAUUAAUCGAGGGAGGGCAGUGAGGCUGUUGGGUGGAACAGUCACACAGAUGGCCCCAGUUUUGUUUUGUUUCACAUUUUCUUUAAAUCUAAGAUACUUCUGUGAAAGUCUACCUCUCAUUUUAAAUAAAGAAUAAAAGAUGUAUUUAAUUCCUGUUCUUUGGGGAUAAUGCAGCAGAGAGGCAGCUGUUCGCUAUGAAUAAUUUUUCUUUUCAUGUAUUUAGCAGUGAGUUCUCAGAAGUAUAUCAGUGUGACAUUCAUGUCCCCUGGGAGGGAAGGGAAGAGGCAGAUAGGAAAUGCCUCAAACUUCUUCUCACUUUGAUGUUUACUUCCUCACUAGAAGCCAAAGGUAAAGGUGUCCAUCUUCAGAAAUAAUGCCUGUAAUAAUCUUUUUAGAGAGUCCAACUAUUUAUAUCCUCUCUAUAGUAAGCAUUUGAAUAUCCAGAACUUCUUUCUGAGGAUCUCUGUUAAAGUUGCCAGAUGAAUUGAAAAAUUGAACUUGCUUUUUUUGUUUAACACAGUGUUCCCUAUAACAAGCCUGUGACUAAUUUUCACUUAAGUGAUUGAACCCAAAUUUAUCUAAUAACAUUUCAGGUGAAAAUUAUAUUGCACCAAAACUUUGACACAAUAUGCAAAAAUAGUAUGAAACUACCCUUUGUUAAUUUAUUCUUAAAUCAAAAUACUAACUUUUAAAAAACAUCAGAAUCAUCAGCAUUGUUCAUCAGUAGUAAAAUGAGCUUCUCAGUCAAGGUCAUACCAAGUCAGUGAAAAGUGUGACUGCAAAAAGGAACAAAAAAAGUGAAAGCAGAAAGUAGAAAUGGGUGAUUUAGCAUGUAAAACCGAUUGCCAGUUGCUUGAUGAUGAAAUCAACAUAGUGAAUACUGUGUCUGCUCCCUCUGCCAAAGCUUCUAGGUCAAAUGGACCCCGUUCCACACCUGGAACCGCUGUACAAAAAGAAGAAUGAGACUCUUUAAAAAUUAUGCACAUACACAUGCACACAUAUAUGUGUGCGUGUGUAUAUAUAUAUAUAUGUGUGUGUGUGUGUAGUUCAUCAGCCAGCUACACAUGAGGACCAAAAUGCUUCAGUCUAAAAUGGAAGAUACACAUUUUUUUCCUUCAAAAUGCAAGUGAGAACUGAAGUAGCUUUUUUAUGGAGUUAAAUGUAAUCUUUCUGUGUACCAGUCUUUGUUGUAUUUUAUAUUUCUUAGGACACAGAUUUCUAGUUGACCACUUAACAUUUGUAACUGAUGAUGUGCUGACCUUUUUUUUUUUUUUUGCCAAACUAGAGAAAAUGUCCAUAUACUUUUGCUGUAAAUGUGUUUAUAUUUAUUUGAAAUGAAACAAAUGGUGAGGAAACAUCCAUUAUUUGUUCUCUAUUUUAAUUGCUAUGUAUCUUAUUUAGAAUAACAAAAAAAAAGUGAAAAAAAAAACACUUGACCCUGGGCUAGCCAAAAGCCCAAGGGCCAAACCUAGCAUUUCCACUGCUAAGGUUUCCAGAUGACCCUCAGGUUCUUCCGCGUUGGUUAGAGAGGGCUACGCAUCUUCUACUGCUCAGCCACAGUCUGUAGCCAGCUUAGAGCUUAGAAGACAUUGCAGUCUGGAUGCCCUUCUGCGAGAUGAAAACUCAGAUGUGUAGUGGAUCAUAUACACAAAGGCAGCACAAAGAAAUAUCUAGAAAUUACCCUAAGUACACUGAAAAGCUCACAUAGUCUCAGUAACCUGAUGAGAAAUGAUGGCAGUGUGUGGGCACAUGUGCCAAAAGGAGAAAUAAAAAUCACCAGCUCAAGUGCUAUUUUCUACUUGAGGAAGAGACAGAAAAGAAAUGUGUCGAAUUAGAGCAGUACUCUCUGACGUUUUAUAAUGAGUUCCAUUUCCACCCUGGAAAUUGCUAUUUUAUAGUGUAUGUGAGAUAUUUCAAAAAUAAUGUUCUAUCAUAUCUGGAUCAAAGACAGAUAACUGUAUUAUAUUUUUCAUCUAGCUAUAAAACUUUAAUCUUACUCUUAAUAUCCUGGAUUUAAUUAAAACUCCUGUUGGGUUCUUCACAAAUGAGAACUUGUUCAAAGGAUUUAUUGAACUGGUAUUGAUUUCACUGAAAAUUUUCCACACCACCACCAUUGUUUUUUUGAAUUCUUGGUGUUGUGCUUCCCACCUUCUGUCCUUUUCGUUUGUUUAGAGAAGAUGAAUUUUUAAAAAGCAGAUAAAUUGCUAAUGAGCAAUAAUGACCUUAUCUUUACCAAAACACUGAAAAUUAAGAGAGGUUCAGUGUUGAAGAAGCACAAUAUGCUGCGGUGUCUUUUUCUAGAAGUGAAUGGAAAUCUUGCUCAGUUGGCAUUUCAAGCAGGAAAUGAAAUGCUUGCUUUAAUGGCAAAGCAGCGUUAACAUUUUUCCUGUCGUGUAGCAGAGAGUACAAGAAUCAUUUCAGCAAAGCAGUGACUCACCAUGAGACGUUAUCUCCAUGGAGCUGCGUUUUGACUUUUCCCACUCUCUUACUCAUAGAAGGAGGACAAAGGAACGAAAUGAAAUCAUGCUCACAAUGAACUGUUCAUUACAUCAACUGAUCUCUCUCUCUCUCUCUUCCUCUCUUUCUCUUUCUCCCAUACCCCAAGGCAAAAUUUUUUUAAAGAAAUGACUUUAAAAACUAUCAUUUCUGUAUUUUAAUUACAUCUCUUAGAAAUAAAAUUAUGUUUGCACCAUAGCUUUCUAAGAAAAAAAAAUGUGUUUUUAACUGAGUCUUAGUUGCUUAGUGCUUUUAUUUGUGUUAUUUUUAGACUGUAUUUUAACCACAACUACAAGGAUCAUGUUUCAUUGCACUUACUUAUUUGCCAGUGUCUGCCUGUCUUUGCUAAAUACAUUACUAUCUCCAAAUUGCCUAAAAUCUGCUAUGAUUCUACAGUAAAUAGCUCAGGGUAUUUCUAUUUAUCACUACUAAAAGGGCACCAUAGUAUGUUUUGGUACUUUAGGCAGUAAACACUGCUUGGUUUAUCAUUUUGUUAUUAAAUUAGAACAAGAACAUCAAAUGGAUUUGCUGCACUAGUUAUUCUUUGUACUGUUGAGCAACUUGGUGUGCUUAUAUGUUGUGUUGGUUGAAGAACUCAUCCGUUUUAUUGUCUUGUAAUAUGAAGUUAGAGUGCCUUUUUAUAUUUGUAUAUUCUGAAAAUGUUCUGUGGAAUGUUUUGUAUUUUUUCAUUUGAGUGUUAUCAGAGCAAUAUGAUACCAGUGAGUUUUCAUUUCAACUUUUCUUUGAAUGUAUAAAGUGUCUUUUUUCCUAUUUCCCCUUGUACUUGCAUUGAAAUGAAUAUGAAAAUGCUUAAGUUUUCUAUAGGAAUUGUUUGAUUUUGCAGUGCUAAAAUGCUUUCGUCUUACGAAACUAUAAACCAUAGGUCAGUAUUAUAGGGGAAAAGCAUUUUAAGAUAGUGACAAUCUGAGUGUUUGUAUAAAAUGUAAUUCUAUGCGUUUCUUAUGUGAUCUAAAAAUUCAAUGCAAAUAUCUUUUAUUUGGUAGUUUUGUCUACAUAUUUUAUGCUCUAGCAUGUGCAAUAUAUCUUUGUAAAGCACGAUGAUACAAAUCUGGUGCCAGUGUUAUAUUUUGCAUAACAUAUUUGUAACAGCAUAAAAUAUUGUUUGAUGAUUUCAGUGGGAUUUUGUCUAUAAUGUUUUCUUAUGUAAAUUGGAGUUGAAUGACUCUGGUAAAUGUCAUGACUGUAAAAAUGGGGAAAAUGACUUUUAGUUCAGUGAAUGACUUUGAAACAAUCUGAAUCUUCUCAAGCACAGUUUAAUACUUUUGCAACUACUGAAUGCUCUAAUAACGUAAUGAAGUACUUAACUGUAAUAUACUAUGGAAAUGCAUUCAGAUGGUUAUUUUUACAAAUAAAAACGGUACAAAUAUUGUUGGAA